AGAGGGGCCGUCGCUCUUCCGGGCGCAUGCGUGCGGCAGCGGCGCCAGGACUGACUGCGCCGUGGAGGCUGCUGCAGUGUUGUGAGUUGGAAGCUGGGGAGCUCGGCAUGGCGGUCCCCGCUGCAGCCAUGGGGCCCUCGGCGUUGGGCCAGAGCGGCCCCGGCUCGAUGGCCCCGUGGUGCUCAGUGAGCAGCGGCCCGUCGCGCUACGUGCUUGGGAUGCAGGAGCUGUUCCGGGGCCACAGCAAGACGCGCGAGUUCCUGGCGCACAGCGCCAAGGUGCACUCGGUGGCCUGGAGUUGCGACGGGCGUCGCCUAGCCUCGGGGUCCUUCGACAAGACGGCCAGCGUCUUCUUGCUGGAGAAGGACCGGUUGGUCAAAGAAAACAAUUAUCGGGGACAUGGGGAUAGUGUGGACCAGCUUUGUUGGCAUCCAAGUAAUCCUGACCUAUUUGUUACGGCGUCCGGAGAUAAAACCAUUCGCAUCUGGGAUGUGAGGACUACAAAAUGCAUUGCCACUGUGAACACUAAAGGGGAGAACAUUAAUAUCUGCUGGAGUCCUGAUGGGCAGACCAUUGCUGUAGGCAACAAGGAUGAUGUGGUGACCUUUAUUGAUGCCAAGACACACCGUUCCAAAGCAGAAGAGCAGUUCAAGUUCGAGGUCAACGAAAUCUCCUGGAACAAUGACAAUAAUAUGUUCUUCCUGACAAAUGGCAAUGGUUGUAUCAACAUCCUCAGCUACCCAGAACUGAAGCCUGUGCAGUCCAUCAACGCCCAUCCUUCCAACUGCAUCUGUAUCAAGUUUGACCCCAUGGGGAAGUACUUUGCCACAGGAAGUGCAGAUGCUUUGGUCAGCCUCUGGGAUGUGGAUGAGUUAGUGUGUGUUCGGUGCUUUUCCAGGCUGGAUUGGCCUGUAAGAACCCUCAGUUUCAGCCAUGAUGGGAAAAUGCUGGCGUCAGCAUCGGAAGAUCAUUUUAUUGACAUUGCUGAAGUGGAGACAGGUAACUUCAUGAGAAUCUACCGUCUUUCACCUUUGGCAGUCAGGACUUCUCUUGUGAUCUCAUCUCUGCAUGUGACUACUUCACCAGCAUGAUCAUGAAUGAAUUUGUCUCCUUUAGACAAGUAUGUUUCUGUUUUGACUGUCACUGCCAGGUGGUGAGGAAGCAAAGAGUUAAGAAAUAAACAGGCAGGUCUGAGGAAAGUGAUUUAGAAAAAUAUUUUGAUUUAUUUAAACUUUAAACUACAGAGUAGAAGGAAGAAAAAAGCACCACUUGGGGUCCCACUCUCUAAAUACCACCUGUUUUAAAUGUUGUGAUAUAUUUCUCUUUAUCUUUUGCCUGUAUAUGAACUUGAAAAAAUAUUAUUUAAAAUUUGAGGAAUUAUAAAGUUUUUGCUUUAAAAACAACAGAAGCUGGAAAUAGAAAAAUGGGAGGAGAGUAUUCAUUUUGCAAAAGAAUUUCCUCAGAUUUGUUUUUUAAUGUUGCUUUAUUGUUUUUGGAAAUCUUUGACACUCUUCGUAAAAAGAUUAAAACUGUAUAGAAAACUUCGAAGAGGAAAGUAAAGAACUUGAAAUUCCACUAUGUAAAGAAUGCAUGCCCCUGUUAGUCACGUUGUGGUGAACAUUGUCCAGCAUCCAGCCAUGCAGAUCCUUCAUGUAACUGCAUGUCCCUGUGACGCGGAGACACUUUCCUGCUCAGUGACCUGCUCUUGAGUUAACCCACCUGUGCUCAGAACCGGCUCUGUCCUCCACUGGCUUGUGGGCUCUCUGUGCCUGGGGGUUCUCUGUAAAAUGAGGUAAUAGUUGUAUCUAUCUCAUGGGAUUAGUAGGUGGAUUAAACCAGUUAAUACUGGUAAGUACUUAA